GCACUCUCUAUCAGGCUUCCUGCAGCGGAGACACCCAUUAGAGAACCCAAGCACAAAGACAAAGCAAAUAGUUGGUCCUGCUCGGAGAACUCUUGGGAUUAUUUAAAGAUCUCCUCUCCUCGGAUUUAGAAAGGCAAAGGCGCAGAGAGCGGGAUGGGAAAUAGCUCCGGAUGGAGGGGCCCAGCAGGGCAGAGGCGAAUGCUAUUUCUCUUCCUGCUCUCUUUGUUAGACCAGGCUCUCUCCGAACCGAUCCGCUACGCUAUUCCCGAGGAGCUGGACAGGGGCUCGCUGGUAGGGAACCUCGCCAAGGACCUGGGGUUUGGCGUGGGGGAUUUACCUACUAGGAACCUGCGGGUUAUUGCAGAGAAGAAAUUCUUUACCGUGAGCCCCGAAAAUGGGAACUUACUUGUGAGCGACCGUAUAGACCGAGAGGAGAUUUGUGGCAAGAAGUCGACGUGUGUUCUGGAAUUUGAAAUGGUUGCUGAAAAGCCUUUAAACUUUUUUCAUGUAACUGUGCUGAUCCAGGAUAUUAACGACAACCCACCGACCUUUAGCCAAAAUAUCACUGAGCUGGAAAUCAGCGAACUGGCUCUCACUGGAGCCACAUUUGCCCUGGAAUCUGCGCAAGAUCCUGAUGUAGGUGUCAAUUCGCUGCAGCAGUACUACCUCAGCCCUGAUCCGCACUUCUCUUUGAUUCAGAAGGAGAACCUGGAUGGCAGUAGGUACCCAGAGCUAGUACUGAAAGCACCCCUGGACAGGGAAGAGCAGCCACAUCACCACCUGGUCCUCACAGCUGUGGAUGGGGGCGAGCCCUCCAGAAGCUGUACCACCCAGAUCAGGGUAAUUGUCGCAGAUGCAAAUGAUAACCCCCCAGUAUUUACUCAGGACAUGUACAGGGUCAAUGUUGCAGAGAACCUGCCCGCUGGCUCCUCCGUAUUAAAAGUGAUGGCCAUUGACAUGGAUGAGGGCAUCAAUGCCGAAAUCAUCUAUGCCUUCAUCAAUAUUGGCAAGGAAGUGAGACAACUGUUCAAGCUGGACAGUAAAACGGGGGAACUCACCACUAUUGGAGAACUGGACUUUGAAGAGAGAGAUAGCUACACAAUUGGGGUGGAAGCAAAGGAUGGUGGACAUCACACUGCAUAUUGUAAAGUACAGAUAGAUAUUUCAGAUGAAAAUGACAAUGCCCCGGAGAUAACCCUGGCUUCUGAAUCCCAACAUAUACAAGAAGAUGCUGAGCUGGGGACUGCCGUUGCCCUGAUCAAAACACAUGAUCUAGAUUCUGGAUUUAAUGGAGAAAUCCUAUGCCAACUAAAAGGAAACUUCCCCUUUAAAAUCGUUCAAGAUACCAAAAACACAUACAGGUUGGUGACAGAUGGAGCCCUGGACCGGGAGCAGAUCCCAGAAUACAAUGUGACGAUCACAGCUACCGACAAAGGCAAUCCACCGCUCUCCUCCAGCAAGACCAUCACUCUGCACAUCCUUGAUGUCAACGACAACGUUCCCGUUUUCCACCAGGCCUCCUACACCGUGCAUGUAGCUGAGAACAAUCCGCCUGGAGCCUCCAUUGCGCAUGUCAGAGCCUCGGAUCCCGACUUGGGACCUAAUGGCCUUGUCUCCUACUACAUCGUGGCCAGUGACCUGGAGCCGCGGGAGCUGUCGUCCUACGUGUCCGUGAGCGCGCGGAGCGGGGUGGUGUUCGCGCAGCGAGCCUUCGACCACGAGCAGCUGCGUGCCUUCGAGCUCACUCUGCAGGCCCGCGACCAGGGCUCGCCUACGCUCAGCGCCAACGUGAGCCUGCGCGUGUUGGUGGACGACCGCAACGACAAUGCACCGCUGGUGCUGUACCCAGCUCUGGGGCCCGAAGGCUCUGCGCUCUUCGAUAUGGUGCCGCGCUCUGCAGAGCCUGGCUACCUGGUGACCAAGGUGGUGGCGGUGGACGCAGACUCGGGAUACAACGCCUGGCUGUCCUACCACAUUGUGCAGGCCAGCGAGCCCGGGCUGUUCAGCCUGGGCCUGCGCACGGGUGAGGUGCGCACGGCGCGUACCUUGGGCGACAGGGAGGCCGCCCGCCAGCGCCUGCUGGUCACUGUGCGUGAUGGAGGACAGCAGCCUCUUUCAGCCACCGUCAUGCUGCACCUAAUCUUCGCAGAUAGCUUGCAAGAGAUACAACCUGACCUUAGCGACCGCCCCACUCCCUCUGACCCUCAGGCGGAGCUACAGUUUCACCUAGUAGUGGCGUUGGCCUUGAUCUCAGUGCUCUUCCUCCUCGCGGUGAUUCUGGCAAUCUCCCUGCGCCUGCGAUGCUCCUCCAGACCCGCCACUGAGGGCUACUUUCAGCCUGGUGUCUGCUUCAAGACUGUACCUGGAGUUCUCCCCACCUACAGCGAAAGGACUUUGCCUUAUUCCUACAAUCCGUGUGCUGCCUCACAUUCCUCAAACACCGAGUUUAAAUUUCUCAAUAUAAAGGCUGAAAAUGCUGCACCACAAGAUCUUCUAUGUGAUGAAGCCUCUUGGUUUGAAAGUAAUGACAAUCCAGAAAUGCCUUCUAAUUCAGGCAAUUUGCAAAAGCAAGCCCCGCCCAACACGGACUGGCGUUUCUCUCAGGCCCAGAGACCCGGCACCAGCGGCUCCCAAAAUGGCGAUGACACCGGCACCUGGCCCAACAACCAGUUUGACACAGAGAUGCUGCAAGCCAUGAUCUUGGCGUCCGCCAGUGAAGCUGCUGAUGGGAGCUCCACCCUGGGAGGGGGUGCCGGCACCAUGGGAUUGAGCGCCCGCUACGGACCCCAGUUCACCCUGCAGCACGUGCCCGACUACCGCCAGAAUGUCUACAUCCCAGGCAGCAAUGCCACACUGACCAACGCAGCUGGCAAGCGGGAUGGCAAGGCCCCAGCAGGUGGCAAUGGCAACAAGAAGAAGUCGGGCAAGAAGGAGAAGAAGUAACAUGGAGGCCAGGCCAAGAGCCACAGGGCGGCCUCUCCCCAACCAGCCCAGCUUCUCCUUACCUGCACCCAGGCCUCAGAGUUUCAGGGCUAACCCCCAGAAUACUGGUAGGGGCCAAGGCCAUGCUCCCCUUGGGAAACAGAAACAAGUGCCCAGUCAGCACCUACCCCUUCCCCCCCAGGGGGUUGAAUAUGCAAAAGCAGUUCCGCUGGGAACCCCCAUCCAAUCAACUGCUGUACCCAUGGGGGUAGUGGGGUUACUGUAGACACCAAGAACCAUUUGCCACACCCCGUUUAGUUACAGCUGAACUCCUCCAUCUUCCAAAUCAAUCAGGCCCAUCCAUCCCAUGCCUCCCUCCUCCCCACCCCACUCCAACAGUUCCUCUUUCCCGAGUAAGGUGGUUGGGGUGUUGAAGUACCAAGUAACCUACAAGCCUCCUAGUUCUGAAAAGUUGGAAGGGCAUCAUGACCUCUUGGCCUCUCCUUUGAUUCUCAAUCUUCCCCCAAAGCAUGGUUUGGUGCCAGCCCCUUCACCUCCUUCCAGAGCCCAAGAUCAAUGCUCAAGUUUUGGAGGACAUGAUCACCAUCCCCAUGGUACUGAUGCUUGCUGGAUUUAGGGAGGGCAUUUUGCUACCAAGCCUCUUCCCAACGCCCUGGGGACCAGUCUUCUGUUUUGUUUUUCAUUGUUUGACGUUUCCACUGCAUGCCUUGACUUCCCCCACCUCCUCCUCAAACAAGAGACUCCACUGCAUGUUCCAAGACAGUAUGGGGUGGUAAGAUAAGGAAGGGAAGUGUGUGGAUGUGGAUGGUGGGGGCAUGGACAAAGCUUGACACAUCAAGUUAUCAAGGCCUUGGAGGAGGCUCUGUAUGUCCUCAGGGGACUGACAACAUCCUCCAGAUUCCAGCCAUAAACCAAUAACUAGGCUGGACCCUUCCCACUACAUAAUAGGGCUCAGCCCAGGCAGCCAGCUUUGGGCUGAGCUAACAGGACCAAUGGAUUAAACUGGCAUUUCAGUCCAAGGAAGCUCGAAGCAGGUUUAGGACCAGGUCCCCUUGAGAGGUCAGAGGGGCCUCUGUGGGUGCUGGGUACUCCAGAGGUGCCACUGGUGGAAGGGUCAGCGGAGCCCCAGCAGGAAGGGUGGGCCAGCCAGGCCAUUCUUAGUCCCUGGGUUGGGGAGGCAGGGAGCUAGGGCAGGGACCAAAUGAACAGAAAGUCUCAGCCCAGGAUGGGGCUUCUUCAACAGGGCCCCUGCCCUCCUGAAGCCUCAGUCCUUCACCUUGCCAGGUGCCGUUUCUCUUCCGUGAAGGCCACUGCCCAGGUCCCCAGUGCGCCCCCUAGUGGCCAUAGCCUGGUUAAAGUUCCCCAGUGCCUCCUUGUGCAUAGACCUUCUUCUCCCACCCCCUUCUGCCCCUGGGUCCCCGGCCAUCCAGCGGGGCUGCCAGAGAACCCCAGACCUGCCCUUACAGUAGUGUAGCGCCCCCUCCCUCUUUCGGCUGGUGUAGAAUAGCCAGUAGUGUAGUGCGGUGUGCUUUUACGUGAUGGCGGGUGGGCAGCGGGCGGCGGGCUCCGCGCAGCCGUCUGUCCUUGAUCUGCCCGCGGCGGCCCGUGUUGUGUUUUGUGCUGUGUCCACGCGCUAAGGCGACCCCCUCCCCCGUACUGACUUCUCCUAUAAGCGCUUCUCUUCGCAUAGUCACGUAGCUCCCACCCCACCCUCUUCCUGUGUCUCACGCAAGUUUUAUACUCUAAUAUUUAUAUGGCUUUUUUUCUUCGACAAAAAAAUAAUAAAACGUUUCUUCUGAAAA